UGAUCCGCCCUUCUCGGCCUCCCAAAGUGCUAGGAUUACAGGCGUGAGCCACGGUGCCCAGCCAAGGUACUUUCUCAUUUAGUUCUUUUAAGAAUCCUGGCAAGUUAGGAGGGUUUUGUUUUGUUUUGUUUCUUUUCAUGGAUAAGGGCUAGAACUUAAAGAGGUUAAGUAAUUUGCCCAGGGUCUCACAGUUUACAUUCCAGGAUUCACAUCCAGGCUUAUCUAACCCCAGAGCCCACACUCGCUCCGUUUGACCAUGGUGUUUUUUCUGUUUACAAAAAUUCUCCAGCAGAGCCUCGUUUCCACGUGGAAGCUCUGUGGGGUUACCACCUCUGAGCACACGCCUGACGAGGCCAGAGAACCUCCCAGCAGCUCCUCUGACGCAGCCAGGGCCAGCGGAGGGGGUGCUGAGGCAUGAAGAGAAGGGCCGAGGGCGAGGCAGCGCUUGCCUCCGUGACGCCUGGCCUUUUGUCCUUGCUCCUUCUCCAGAGACUUUGCUGUGGUUCUGCCCCGUGAUUUCACCAGGUCAGCGAGGUUUUAGUUGUGUAACAGGAUGUCACGUGGGAUGUUUUUCUUUUUCUCUGGAAUUAGUGAGUAGGUGGUUCCUACUCGCUGAGUCCUGGGAGGGGUCACCUAGGAAAGUCAGUGGUAGAGAUGAGGGGUGCUUGAGAGAGGGGAAUCGGGGGUCUCACACUUGCUGGUGGCCGUCAUGGCAGCAACCAGAGUGAAGAGAACUGGGGCGAGGGCAGUGUCCAGUGGCCGUGGAGCAAUCUGUGCUCCCUCCUUUUGGCAGGGCAAGGAUGGAGAAAUUUCCUGUGGGUCCAGUGGAGCCUGAGGAAGGAAGUUGAGCAUGAGCCAUCUUGCUUCAGCAUUCCUAAAAGGGCUCAGCCGCCGGGUGUCUUCAGCUGUAGGUGACUGGGGUGGGUGUGCUGGUGAGGGAAGUUGAGCGUACUGGAAUAGACUCAAGCCAAGGCGCAUCUCCUUUUUCAGUGAGAUGUGUACUCCCUACCUCCAAAAACCUGCAUCUAUACCUUGGGAGAUUGAGCACUUGGACGCUAUGCCAGAGAGGGAAGUGGUGACCAACUCAUGUCAACCGAUGAAGAGAGAAUUGGAACCCUGCCGAGCUUUCCAAAGAGAAAUUUACCUCUUCUCUUCUCCCUCCUCUGCACCCAUCCUCCCAGUACACAGAUAGGGCCUACAAUAAAGAGGAGAGGGAGGGUGGGCCGGAGCAAACCCCUCAGCAGUCCACACAGCCUGUAAGGCGGCGGGGAAGAGCUAAUUUUGCGUCACAUACGGGACUGGAAUUCUAAGUUAGGCCGGAUGGAGAUUUUCUAUCUGAAUCUUAAUGCAAUGGCAAAUCGUGCUGCAGGGAAAGGCUAUGAGAAUGAAGACAAUUAUUCCAAUAUCAAGUUUCAGUUUAUCGGGAUAGAGAACAUCCAUGUCAUGAGGAACAGUCUGCAGAAAAUGCUGGAAGUGUGUGAACUUAAAUCUCCCUCCAUGAGUGAUUUCCUGUGGGGUCUGGAGAACUCUGGCUGGUUAAGGCACAUUAAAGCCAUAAUGGAUGCAGGAAUCUUCAUUGCAAAGGCAGUGUCAGAGGAAGGGGCAAGUGUGCUUGUUCACUGUUCUGAUGGCUGGGACAGGACCGCUCAGGUGUGCUCGGUGGCAAGCCUGCUGCUGGACCCUCACUACCGGACUCUGAAGGGCUUCAUGGUAUUAAUUGAAAAGGACUGGAUUUCCUUUGGUCAUAAGUUUAAUCACCGAUAUGGCAAUCUAGAUGGUGACCCAAAAGAAAUCUCUCCAGUUAUUGACCAGUUCAUUGAGUGUGUUUGGCAGUUAAUGGAACAAUUUCCCUGUGCCUUUGAGUUCAAUGAGAGGUUUUUGAUUCACAUUCAACAUCACAUUUAUUCCUGCCAGUUUGGAAACUUCCUAUGUAACAGCCAAAAGGAGAGACGAGAACUCAAGAUUCAAGAAAGAACAUACUCAUUAUGGGCUCACCUGUGGAAGAAUCGGGCCGACUACCUGAAUCCUCUGUUUAGAGCUGAUCACAGCCAGACUCAGGGAACCCUUCAUCUCCCUACAACACCAUGUAACUUCAUGUACAAGUUUUGGAGUGGAAUGUAUAACCGCUUUGAAAAGGGGAUGCAGCCCCGACAGUCAGUUACAGAUUACCUAAUGGCAGUGAAGGAAGAAACUCAGCAGCUAGAGGAAGAACUAGAGGCCCUGGAAGAAAGGCUGGAAAAAAUUCAAAAGGUCCAGUUAAAUUGCACUAAGGUGAAGAGUAAGCAAAGUGAGCCCAGCAAGCACUCAGGGUUUUCUACCUCAGACAACAGCAUAGCCAACACUCCCCAGGAUUACAGUGGGAAUAUGAAAUCAUUUCCAUCCCGGAGCCCUUCACAAGGCGAUGAAGAUUCUGCUCUGAUUCUAACCCAAGACAAUCUGAAAAGUUCAGAUCCAGAUCUGUCAGCCAACAGUGACCAAGAGUCCGGGGUGGAGGAUUUGAGCUGUCGGUCUCCAAGUGGUGGUGAGCAUGCACCGAGUGAAGAUAGUGGCAAGGACCGGGAUUCUGAUGAAGCCGUGUUUCUCACUGCCUGAAGUUUCCCUUUGGAGUUCCAAAGUAAAGGACACAUAAGCAACACUUCCAAAAACAAGGGAACAAGGUGGUUUAUUGUAAAAACAGGAAAUGGUGCAUGUCAUUGAGAACUACUUUAAUGCAGCUAUGAAAAGGGAAAAAAGUGCCCAGUUCUUGAUUUCUUAGAUACUGAAGAGGACGUAGUCAUUUCAUUUAUCAAAUAUAAGGAAAAUUAUUCACCAUUUUGAAGCUCACCCUAGACUAUGAAAAUUAUAUUCACUGCAGAGCAAUUACUUCUGUCAUUACCUGAAGUGAUCAGUAUCUAUCUUCCUUGUCAUAGCAUGCAUCUCUCAAAAAGCCUCCACUCCUUUCCCUCACAUCUGUGAUCAUCAUGAUUCUUUUAGUUCACUUCUAGAUGCAUAUUUUGUGUUUUCUAAAGCAUCUGACAUUAUCCUCCUUUCCGACCCUCUUAUACAUAUUUCUAAAAACAGGCACAUUGGUGAGAUGCACCCUUUUUAGUUAAUAGAUGCAUUCCUAAGGAGCUUUUAAUUGCUUAUCUUUCAGGCAUAAUCAUCACUUUAACUUUUCCUUGGAGCAUAUAUUUUGAAUUGUGAGAAUAAUUUUGUUGCUUUUCUCUGAGAUCUAUAGUCUGUUUCUCCUCAUUAUUUAAAAAUGCUAAACCUUGUAUCUCACUUUUUCUCUAACACUGAUUUAAUAGCUAACGAGGUAGAAGCAACAUUCAUUCUCCUGGUCUUACAUAUGAAUUUAAGUAUCAGCUUUCUUGUAAUAACCUUUUAUUACUGUUCUAGAGACUACACUACCGACAGUGUGGGCCAGCCACCAGCCUGAUCUCAAAGUAUCACAUUAUAAAGUUAGUAGAUAAAACAUCUGUGAGUGAAAAUCCAGUUUCAAGAACCAGAGAAUUGGGUUGUCAUGUCUGUUUAAUGAAGGGAAUAGGUUUUGUAAUCUAUCAUUUUAGAAAUUAUGUAACUGGCUAAUAUGGUUUAAUUAACCUUAGUAACAUCUCAUGACCACUGACUGCUGAAAGUUCUGAAAAGAAUUUUUGUUUUGUUACACUGCACAUUUAAGGGAGAGUCCCUCCCCUAUCUUAUGAGUUAAAAAAGACUUCACUAGGUGACCUAAAUUAAACUUAGUGGGGAAAAGUGGCCAUGUUUGGACAUAAAUAAAUGGUAUUCACACUGUAUGGUUUUAAUAUAUUAGUACAUUCUAGAAUGUAAAAGGAUUAAACUUUACAAUUUAGAUCAAUAUUUUGAAUAUGUGAAAGGAUUAAUUUAAACUUUACAAUUUACAUCAAUAUUUUGAAUAUCUGAUUUUUUUUAAUGGGAGAAUUAUUACAUUUCGCUGAAAUGAGGACGAGGGCAAGAAAGCAACAUUGCUGAUCUCUCUAGUAUGAAAGAUUUGGAGGGAGUGUUGCAAUAUAUAUAAAUGAAAACAUUUAAUUGUGUUCAUCAUAUUUAAAAAUAUAGAAUAUAUUAGAGAACUGUGAUUUAAAAGUACUGUUAAUGUAAAAAAUAAAGCAAGUGUAAUUAAUUCUUUCAGAAUAUAAAAUUUGGGCAUUCUCUGCUGAGCAGUUCCCAAAUUAAGUACAAGGAAUGUUUAUUCAUUUUCUGCAAUAUACUAUAUGUAAUAGGGAAUACCUUGCUAAAAUAAAACUUAGGAUAUAGUGGUAAUGGCUUUCACAUUUUUAUAACAUAACAUAACUCACUUCACAACCUUCUUGGAGCUGUCCACUCUUAGAAACUCUGUUGCCUAAUAUUGAGGAUGUGGCUUUAAUUUCUUCCGUUUGACAGUGUAUGUCUAUAAAAACAAUAAACAUUUUUUAAAAAAUGACAAAGUAUCUAUGCCAAACAGCACUAUGCUUUUAUUUGAAAAGCAAAUAGUAUAAAUAUUUGAUGUUUUAAAAUGUAGUUUUUUAAUAUGACAACUUCCAUAUCAGAGUCAUAAACUUUUAGUCCCCUCAACUUUUUUACAAGACAGACAUUAUAAUUUAUGUAACAUGUUCGUCUGCUUAUUAGAAGUUAACCUAGCACUGAGAUUUAUAUAAAAGGUUACAUUUAUUGCUUAUUAAAACUUUACUGUACUUUCACAGAUUCUUCAGAGCAUGGCUAACCCAACAAGACUAAAAUAUCCCCAACAAGACUAAAAUAUCUAAUAAUCAAACAUUAAUCAGGAAGUGUUUUAUUGAGAGCAGUGGUUUAAAGCAUAGGGAAUAAUCCAGUAUAAAACUGAUUUGAGGCAUAUUACUUCCCAAUUAGUAAUAUAUAGAAUGCAAGUAAUUUAUUUUUUAAAGUUGAUAUGAAAUAAAUAGGUAAGAAUUUUGACCAUGACCCAGCAAAUCAGUAACUGAGCUUUUUAUAGAAUGGAAGGUGAUGAUCAGAGACAGAAACCAUAGAAUAAAUUUUUAUUCUUUAAGAGCACAUUAGUUUACUUUCUUCUCCUAAAAAUGAAUCUGAGCUGUCCUUCAAUUUAAGCAUAUAUAUGUGUCAAGCACCCUCUAUUCUGAUAUAAAUUUCCUAGUCUCAAUUUAUGCCUAGAAAUUUCUUUCAACUUUGAAGUGGGUCUGUUUAGUUUAUAUCUCACUGAUUGAUUGAUUUAGAAUUUUCUUCUAUUUUAAGAUAUUAACCUUUAAAUCUCUACCUAUGACAAAUUCGUACACUGAUUAGCCUAGUAACUCCUAAGUAUUCCUCUUUAAUUCUGAUUUCUAUCUCAUCUUGUAAAAUCAGAAUACAAACUUUCACAUGCAUUUCAUUUUUCCUGUGGCACUGCUUCUCCGAUGUGACCAAUUUUUAUGAAGAAAAUAUAUAGCCAUAAAAUUAGAAAAAAUGGUCACUUAAUCUCUGUUGCAAAAACAGAACCCACAUUCAUACGGGCAUAUUCAAAUGCAGAUUCUUUUCAUCGUGGGUGACAUACAUAACCUUUAUGUAAACUGAUUUGUCUAUUUGUUAAAUGCAGAUAACUGAUCACACUGCUCUGUUUCAUGACUGGGUUGUAACAAGGUUAUCCAAUGAAUGGUAUAGAAUGAAACUGGGAUAGUUCAACUUUAAAGAAUAAAAAACACUGAGAUGAACUA